GUUCCCCCCGGACAGCCCUACGCCGGCAAAGGUCUCGAGAUGCAGGCGGCCCUAGAGGUCACCGCUCGCUACUGUGGCCGGGAGCUGGAGCAGUAUGGCCAGUGUGUGGCGGCCAAGCCGGAAUCCUGGCAGCGGGACUGUCACUACCUUAAGAUGAGCAUUGCCCAGUGCACAUCCUCCCACCCAAUCAUCCGCCAGAUCCGCCAGGCCUGUGCUCAGCCUUUUGAGGCCUUCGAGGAGUGUCUUCGACAGAACGAGGCAGCUGUGGGCAACUGUGCAGAGCAUAUGCGCCGCUUCCUGCAGUGCGCUGAGCAGGUGCAGCCGCCACGCUCACCUGCAACUGUGGAGGUAAGAGGGGCUCACCUCAGUUCAUCUCUUUUCUCCAUAACAUCCCCUUCAUCCUUCUGGUUGUUCAGGGUAAAGACUUUGGAGUCAUCCUCAGCCCCACCCCAUCACCACACAGGCCUUUGCCAUGCAUCCAGAAUCCAGAACAUCAUCACUUCUUGCCCCAUAUAGCCCCUGCUUUAAUCCACCACCACCCUCACCCUCCACCUCCAGGAUACCUGCCCCAGCCUUCUCCCUGGUCUCCCUUCCUCCCUCUUUUCUUGCCUCCAUAAAGCGGCCUGGGUGAGCAUGUAAGGACUGAAAUCUGGUCUCAUCACACCUAUGCUUAAAGCUCUCCAGUGGCUUUGUGUCACAUUGAGAACAAAAGUCCAGGUCCUUGCUGGGUUCUCUGUGUUCUUCCCUAGGCUGACUUCAUCUGCCUCCUGCCUCACCCUCUCUCUUCUUUCUCACUACUCCUCAUCUGCAACUGCAGAGGGGCUGGGCUGGGGUGGCCAAAAAAAGGUCACUCUUUUAAAUGUAUCUAAUAUGUAAACCAGAUAUACAGUAUAUCUGUGAUAUGUAAGUUUCAUGGUUGGGCAAUUAGAACAAAAGUCUAAAAUGACUCCUUGAGGAGAGGCAGUAACGGAAAAAGGUUGAAAAAUGCUCUUUUAGAUGUUUACUACCCUCCUCACUGGACUGUGAGCUCCAAAGGUGAAAGUCACAUCUUUCCCCAGCCCCUGUGAGUACCCUCUCCUGGGGCCCUCUCUCUGCCCCUGCAGCCCUGGCUUCUCUCUUGGGCCACCUGGCCAUCCUUCUCCUGGGCCCCAUGCUCCAUCUUGACUUUCCAGUCAUUCUUGGUGAUCAUCCUAGACUGAUCUCAGAGGAAAUCUGACCAUGUUCUGCUUCUACUUACAAACCUUUCCAUGGUUCUCAAUUCCACCAGCCCAAGUCUUAAUGCCAGCACAGCCCACAGGGCCCUGUGGGAUGCAGUCCCUGCGACCCGUGGUCCCACCUCUCCUCUCUUUCCCCCUUAAGCUCUAUGUUCCAGCCCCAGUGAACAUGCAGUUACUCAAGUGCACGUCUCCGCUGCUUUUGUCCAGCUGUUUCCCUCUGCUGGGACUGCCCUUCCUAAUCCAUCUCCUGGCUAAUUCCUAUUCCAGCUUAGACGGCACGUCUCUCAGAAAACCUCCCUGAUGUCCCACCCACUUCCCGCCCCUGUCUUCAAGUUCCCAAGGUCCCUGAGCCCCUCCAUCAAGGCUCACAUCCUAUGCCUGUGUCAAGGGAGCUCUUGGCUGAAGAUUGGGGUGAUGCCCUUCUUACCAGGCCCUAUAGGCAUUAAUUGUUUCUGUAAGGCAAGGAUAAGUGAAUAGUUCAGACCCCUAGGGCAGAAACUACGACCCCUGAGAGCCGGAAGGAACUUAAUUCUCCUCAGGAAACGUUACCUAACGAUCACAUACUGUUCUCAGUCAGCUGCUGGGGACAUUUCUGUCUUUCAAGUUUUUUGGGCAUCUGAACAGUAAAGACCCCAUCCUCCUAUCUUAGAGCCAUUUGCUGCUUCCCUCCCUGGACCAGCAACCAGCCUCUCUCUGGUCUCCUUGUGGCCACCCCUGCCCUGACAGUCUUCUCUUCCCUGGCAGCCAAAGAAGCUUUUAAAAAUGGGAAUUAGGGCCGGGUGCGGUGGCACAUGCCUGUAAUCCCAGCACUUGGGGAGGCCGAGGUGGGUGGAUCACCUGAGGUCAGGAGUUUGAGACCAGCCUGGCCAACAUGGUGAAACCCCAUCUCUACUAAAAAUACAAAUAUUAGCCAGGUGUGGUGGCAGGUACCUGUAAUCCCAGCUACUUGGGAGGCUGAGGCAGGAGAAUUGCUUGAACCCAGGAGGCAGAGGUUGCAGUGAGCCAAGAUUGCACCAUUGCACUCUAGCCUGGGCGAUAGAGCGAGACUCUGUCUUCCAAAAAAAAAAAAAAAAGGGAAUUAGGUCACAUCUCCUCAUCAUCCCCUCCUUCCUGGGGAUGGCAUCCCAGUUACAGUUUUUCCUUCCUAGCUAGGGGCAGUGAGAUUUGUUGUCUGGUCUACACAAUAGCGAACACAAACAUUCUCAUCUCCUGCAGCAUGGCAUACAGACUUUACAGAAUGUCCUGUGUUUUUGUGGCUGACAAUCAAAGUGGUACAUGUCCCUCCCAUUCCGCACACACCUCUGCUCUUUACCCUGAUUAAAUUUUCUUCAUCGAA